GUUCUCCGCCCCUGCCACUGGGCCAUGGAGACUGUGGCACAGUAGACUGUAGUGUGAGGCUCGCGGGGGCAGUGGCCAUGGAGGCCGUGCUGAACGAGCUGGUGUCUGUGGAGGACCUGCUGAAGUUUGAAAAGAAAUUUCAGUCUGAGAAGGCAGCAGGCUCGGUGUCCAAGAGCACGCAGUUUGAGUACGCCUGGUGCCUGGUGCGGAGCAAGUACAAUGAUGACAUCCGUAAAGGCAUCGUGCUGCUCGAGGAGCUGCUGCCCAAAGGGAGCAAGGAGGAACAGCGGGAUUACGUCUUCUACCUGGCCGUGGGGAACUACCGGCUCAAGGAAUACGAGAAGGCCUUAAAGUACGUCCGCGGGUUGCUGCAGACAGAGCCCCAGAACAACCAGGCCAAGGAACUGGAGCGGCUCAUUGACAAGGCCAUGAAGAAAGAUGGACUCGUGGGCAUGGCCAUCGUGGGAGGCAUGGCCCUGGGUGUGGCGGGACUGGCCGGACUCAUCGGACUUGCUGUGUCCAAGUCCAAAUCCUGAAGGAGACGCGGGAGCCCACGGAGAACGCUCCAGGAGGGCCUGUCCAUCCUCGCUGUCCUUUCCCUGUUCUCCCCCUGCCCCCCGUCUCUAUCCUCUGUGGCCUUCAGCUAAUUUCUGCUCCCCUGAGAUUCGUCCUUCAGCCCCAUCAUGUGCUUUGGGAUGAGUGUAAAUAAAACGGGGCUGUGGCUUGGGAACCCCCGUGUCUGCGUUGAGGGGAGGGGUGGGUUCUGAACGCUGGGCACAGGGGGCGGAGACGUCACUCCUGGUCCUCUCCUGCCCCUGCCCUCCAGGUUGGCACGGGGUUCUUUGUCCACCCCGCAGCCCAGAGCCCACA